AGUUUGAGGAGCGGCCGGAGUGUGGGCUGCUGGUAGGCAGCCUGCUGGUCCUGGGCCCUCGGAGGGAGGUGAGACCCGGCAGCCCCUGCCUCCCAGCCUGUGCCCCCAGCCUGCGUGCUGCCCAGAGCCCCCAUAGAGAGAGGUCCCCGCCGCCACCCUCAUGGAUCAGCCACAGUUCAGCGGGGCGCCCCGCUUUCUCACCCGGCCCAAGGCCUUCGUGGUGUCGGUGGGCAAGGACGCCACCCUCAGCUGCCAGAUCGUGGGUAAUCCCACGCCACAGGUGAGCUGGGAGAAGGACCAGCAGCCGGUGGCGGCCGGCGCGCGCUUCCGUCUGGCCCAGGACGGCGACCUCUACCGCCUCACUAUCCUGGACCUGGCGCUGGGCGACAGUGGGCAAUACGUGUGCCGCGCGCGCAAUGCCAUAGGCGAGGCCUUCGCUGCUGUGGGCCUGCAGGUGGACGCGGAGGCCGCGUGCGCCGAGCAGGCGCCGCACUUCCUGCUGCGGCCCACGUCCAUCCGCGUGCGCGAGGGCUCAGAGGCCACCUUCCGCUGCCGCGUGGGUGGCUCCCCGAGGCCGGCAGUGAGCUGGUCCAAGGACGGGCGGCGCCUGGGUGAGCCCGACGGCCCCCGCGUGCGCGUGGAGGAGCUCGGCGAGGCAAGUGCGCUGCGCAUUCGGGCGGCGCGGCCGCGCGACGGCGGCACUUACGAGGUCCGCGCCGAGAACCCGCUGGGCGCUGCCAGCGCCGCCGCGGCGCUAGUGGUGGACUCGGACGCCGCGGACACGGCCAGCCGGCCCGGGACCUCCACGGCCGCGCUCCUGGCGCACCUGCAGCGGCGGCGCGAGGCUAUGCGCGCCGAGGGCGCCCCCGCCUCACCGCCCAGCACCGGCACGCGCACCUGCACGGUGACUGAAGGCAAGCACGCGCGCCUCAGCUGCUACGUGACCGGCGAGCCCAAGCCCGAGACGGUGUGGAAGAAGGACGGCCAGCUGGUGACCGAGGGCCGGCGCCACGUGGUGUACGAGGACGCGCAGGAGAACUUCGUGCUCAAGAUCCUCUUCUGCAAGCAGUCGGACCGCGGCCUCUACACCUGCACGGCGUCCAACCUCGUGGGCCAGACCUACAGCUCUGUGCUGGUCGUAGUGCGCGAGCCCGCGGUUCCCUUCAAAAAGCGGCUGCAAGAUCUGGAGGUGCGGGAGAAGGAGUCGGCCACGUUCCUAUGUGAGGUGCCCCAGCCGUCCACUGAGGCCGCGUGGUUCAAGGAGGAGACGCGGUUGUGGGCGAGCGCCAAGUACGGCAUCGAGGAGGAGGGCACCGAGCGCCGCCUGACCGUGCGCAAUGUCUCGGCCGACGACGACGCGGUGUACAUCUGCGAGACGCCAGAGGGCAGCCGCACGGUGGCGGAGCUCGCAGUCCAAGGAAACCUCCUCCGAAAGCUCCCUCGGAAGACGGCGGUGCGCGUGGGCGACACGGCUAUGUUUUGCGUGGAGCUGGCGGUCCCGGUGGGCCCCGUCCACUGGCUGCGGAACCAGGAGGAAGUGGUGGCGGGGGGCCGCGUGGCCAUCUCCGCGGAGGGCACGCGCCACACACUAACCAUCUCCCAGUGCUGCCUGGAGGAUGUGGGCCAGGUGGCCUUUAUGGCUGGCGACUGCCAGACGUCCACCCAGUUCUGCGUGUCGGCCCCCAGGAAGCCUCCCCUGCAACCCCCUGUGGAUCCUGUGGUAAAGGCCAGGAUGGAGAGUUCCGUGAUUCUCAGCUGGUCCCCACCACCCCAUGGGGAACGCCCUGUCACUAUCGACGGCUACCUGGUAGAGAAGAAGAAGCUUGGCACCUACACCUGGAUCAGGUGCCACGAGGCUGAAUGGGUGGCUACACCUGAGCUGACCGUGGCUGAUGUGGCGGAGGAGGGGAACUUCCAGUUCCGAGUGUCCGCUCUCAACAGCUUUGGUCAGAGUCCCUACCUCGAGUUCCCGGGGACUGUCCACCUGGCCCCCAAGCUGGCCGUGAGGACACCGCUGAAGGCGGUGCAGGCGGUAGAGGGUGGCGAGGUCACUUUCUCCGUGGACCUCACGGUGGCCUCAGCGGGUGAGUGGUUCCUGGAUGGGCAGGCCCUGAAGGCCAGCAGUGUGUAUGAGAUCCACUGUGAUCGCACCCGGCACACGCUCACCAUCCGGGAGGUGCCCGCCAGCCUGCACGGGGCGCAGCUGAAGUUCGUGGCCAACGGCAUUGAGAGCAGCAUCCGGAUGGAGGUCCGGGCGGCCCCAGGGCUGACUGCCAACAAGCCGCCAGCCGCAGCUGCCCGGGAGGUGCUGGCUCGGCUGCACGAGGAGGCGCAGCUGCUGGCUGAGCUGUCAGAUCAGGCUGCGGCUGUGACGUGGCUGAAGGAUGGUCGCACACUGUCCCCAGGCCCCAAGUAUGAGGUGCAGGCAUCGGCCGGGCGGCGGGUGCUCCUUGUGCGAGAUGUGGCCCGGGACGAUGCAGGCCUCUACGAGUGCGUCAGCCGCGGGGGCCGCAUCGCCUACCAGCUCUCCGUGCAAGGCCUCGCGCGCUUUCUGCACAAGGACAUGGCGGGCAGCUGUGUGGAUGCCGUGGCUGGGGGCCCGGCGCAGUUUGAGUGUGAGACCUCCGAAGCCCACGUCCACGUGCACUGGUACAAGGAUGGCAUGGAGCUGGGCCACUCCGGUGAGCGCUUCUUGCAGGAGGAUGUGGGGACGCGGCACCGGCUGGUGGCAGCCACAGUCACCAGGCAGGAUGAAGGCACCUACUCCUGCCGCGUGGGCGAGGACUCUGUGGACUUCCGGCUCCGCGUCUCUGAGCCCAAGGCGGUGUUUGCCAAGGAGCAGCCGGCGUGCAGGGAGGUGCAGGCUGAGGUGGGGGCCAGCGCCACGCUGAGCUGUGAGGUGGCCCAGGACCAGAUGGAGGUGACGUGGUACAAGGACGGGAAGAAGUUGAGCUCCAGCUCGAAAGUGCACGUGGAGGCUGUGGGCUGUAUGCGGAGGCUGGUGGUGCAGCAGGUGGGCCAGGCAGACUCCGGAGAGUACAGCUGUGAGGCCAGGGGACAGAGGGUCUCCUUCCGCCUGGACGUUGCAGAGCCCAAGGUGGUGUUUGCUAAGGAGCAGCUGGCACGCAGGAAGCUGCAGGCAGAGGCAGGAGCCAGUGCCACACUGAGCUGCGAGGUGGCCCAGGCCCAGACGGAGGUGACGUGGUACAAGGAUGGGAAGAAGCUGAGCUCCAGCUCGAAAGUGUGCAUGGAGGCCACAGGCUGCACGCGCAGGCUGGUUGUGCAGCAGGCAGGCCAGGCGGAUGCCGGGGAGUAUAGCUGCGAGGCUGGGGGCCAGCGGCUCUCCUUCCAUCUGGAUGUCAAAGAGCCCAAGGUGGUGUUUGCCAAGGACCAGGUGGCACACAGUGAGGUGCAGGCUGAGGCAGGGGCCAGUGCCACGCUGAGCUGCGAGGUGGCCCAGGCCCAGACGGAGGUGAUGUGGUACAAAGAUGGGAAGAAGCUGAGCUCCAGCUUGAAAGUGCAUGUAGAGGCCAAGGGCUGCAGACGGAGGCUGGUGGUGCAGCAGGCAGGCAAGACAGAUGCCGGGGACUACAGCUGCGAGGCCAGGGGCCAGAGGGUCUCCUUCCGCCUGCACAUCACAGAGCCCAAGAUGAUGUUUGCAAAGGAGCAGUCAGUGCAUAAUGAGGUGCAGGCUGAGGCGGGGGCCAGUGCCAUGCUGAGCUGUGAGGUGGCCCAGGCCCAGACGGAGGUGACGUGGUACAAGGAUGGGAAGAAGCUGAGCUCCAGCUCAAAAGUGGGCAUGGAGGUCAAAGGGUGCACACGGAGGCUGGUGCUGCCACAGGCGGGCAAAGCAGAUGCUGGGGAGUACAGCUGUGAGGCUGGGGGCCAGAGAGUCUCCUUCCACCUGCACAUCACAGAGCCCAAGGGGGUGUUUGCGAAGGAGCAGUCAGUGCAUAAUGAGGUGCAGGCUGAGGCGGGGACCACUGCCAUGCUGAGCUGUGAGGUGGCCCAGCCCCAGACAGAGGUGACGUGGUACAAGGACGGGAAGAAGCUGAGCUCCAGCUCAAAAGUACGCAUGGAGGUCAAGGGCUGCACACGAAGGCUGGUAGUGCAGCAGGUGGGCAAAGCAGAUGCUGGGGAGUACAGCUGCGAGGCUGGGGGCCAGAGAGUCUCCUUUCAACUGCACAUCACAGAGCCCAAGGCAGUGUUUGCCAAGGAGCAGUUGGUGCAUAAUGAGGUGCGGACUGAGGCAGGGGCCAGUGCCACACUGAGCUGUGAGGUGGCCCAGGCCCAGACAGAGGUGACGUGGUACAAGGAUGGGAAGAAGCUGAGCUCCAGUUCGAAAGUGCGCAUAGAGGCUGCGGGCUGCAUGCGGCAGCUGGUGGUGCAGCAGGCAGGCCAGGCAGAUGCUGGGGAGUACACCUGUGAGGCUGGGGGCCAGCGGCUCUCCUUCCACCUGGAUGUUUCAGAGCCCAAGGCGGUGUUUGCAAAGGAGCAGCUGGCACACAGGAAGGUGCAGGCCGAGGCGGGGGCCAUUGCCACGCUGAGCUGCGAGGUGGCCCAGGCCCAGACAGAGGUGACGUGGUACAAGGACGGGAAGAAGCUGAGCUCCAGCUCGAAAGUUCGAAUGGAGGCUGUGGGCUGCACACGGAGGCUGGUGGUGCAGCAGGCAUGCCAGGCGGACACCGGGGAGUAUAGCUGCGAGGCCGGGGGCCAGCGGCUCUCCUUCAGCCUGGACGUGGCAGAGCCCAAGGUGGUGUUUGCCAAGGAGCAGCCAGUGCACAGGGAGGUGCAGGCCCAGGCGGGGGCCAGCACCACACUCAGCUGCGAGGUGGCUCAGGCCCAGACGGAGGUGAUGUGGUACAAGGACGGGAAGAAGCUGAGCUUCAGCUCGAAAGUGCGCAUGGAGGCUGUGGGCUGCACACGGAGGCUGGUGGUGCAGCAGGCGGGCCAGGCGGUCGCCGGGGAGUACAGCUGCGAGGCGGGGAGCCAGCGGCUCUCCUUCCACCUGCACGUGGCAGAGCCCAAGGCGGUGUUUGCUAAGGAGCAGCCAGCACACAGGGAGGUGCAGGCUGAAGCAGGGGCUAGCGCCACACUGAGCUGUGAGGUGGCCCAGGCCCAGACAGAGGUGACUUGGUACAAGGACGGGAAGAAGCUGAGCUCCAGCUUGAAAGUGCAUGUGGAGGCUGCAGGCUGUACACGGAGGCUGGUGGUGCAGCAGGCAGGCCAGGCAGACACCGGAGAGUAUAGCUGUGAGGCUGGGGGCCAGCAGCUCUCCUUCCGCCUGCAAGUGGCAGAGCCCAAGGCGGUGUUUGCCAAGGAGCAGCCAGCGAGCAGGGAGGUGCAGGCUGAGGCGGGGACCAGUGCCACGCUGAGCUGCGAGGUGGCCCAGGCCCAGACAGAGGUGACGUGGUACAAGGACGGGAAGAAACUGAGCUCCAGCUCGAAAGUGCGAAUGGAGGCCGUGGGCUGCACACGGAGGCUGGUGGUGCAGGAGGCAGGCCAGGCGGACGCCGGGGAGUACAGCUGCAAGGCCGGGGAUCAGCGGCUGUCCUUCCACCUGCACGUGGCAGAGCCCAAGGUGGUGUUUGCCAAGGAGCAGCCAGCACACAGGGAGGUGCAGGCUGAGGCGGGGGCCAGUGCCACGCUGAGCUGCGAGGUGGCCCAGGCCCAGACAGAGGUGACGUGGUACAAGGAUGGGAAGAAGCUGAGUUCCAGCUCGAAAGUGCGCGUGGAGGCCGUGGGCUGCACACGGAGGCUGGUGGUGCAGCAGGCGGGCCAGGCAGAGGCCGGGGAGUACAGCUGCGAGGCAGGGGGUCAGCAGCUCUCCUUCCGCCUGCAGGUGGCAGAGCCCAAGGCGGUGUUUGCCAAGGAGCAGGUGGUGUUUGCCAAGGAUCAGCCGGUGCACAGGGAGGUGCAGGCUGAGGCAGGGACCAGCACCAUGCUGAGCUGCGAGGUGGCCCAAGCCCAGACGGAGGUUAUGUGGUACAAGGACGGGAAGAAGCUGAGCUCCAGCUCGAAAAUGCGUGUGGAGGCCGUGGGCUGCACACGGAGGCUGGUGGUGCAGGAGGCAGGCCAGGCGGACGCCGGGGAGUACAGCUGCGAGGCUGGGGGCCAGCGGCUCUCCUUCCAUCUGCAUGUGGCUGAGCCCAAGGUGGUGUUUGCCAAGGAGCAGCCGGCAUGCAGGGAGGUGCAGGCGGAGGCGGGGGCCAGUGCCACGCUGAGCUGUGAGGUGGCCCAGGGCCAGAUGGAGGUGACAUGGUACAAGGACGGGAAGAAGCUGAGCUCCAGCUCAAAAGUGCACAUGGAGGCCAGCGGCUACACACGGAGGCUGGUAGUGCAGCAGGCGGGCCAGGCGGAUGCUGGGGAGUACAGCUGUGAGGCGGGGGGCCAACGGCUGUCCUUCCGCCUGCACGUGGCAGAGCUGGAGCCCCAAAUUUCAGAGAGACCCUGCCGCAGGGAGCCUCUGGUGGUCAAGGAGCAUGAAGACAUCAUCCUGACCGCCACACUGGCCACACCCUCUGCGGCCACGGUGACCUGGCUCAAGGAUGGUGUGGAGAUUCGCCGCAGCAAGCGGCAUGAGACAGCCAGCCAGGGGGACACCCACACCCUGACCGUGCAUGGCGCCCAGGUUCUGGACAGCGCCAUCUACAGCUGCCGUGUGGGCGCAGAGGGGCAGGACUUCCCAGUGCAGGUGGAAGAGGUGGCCGCCAAGUUCUGCCGGCUGCUGGAGCCUGUGUGCGGCGAGCUGGGUGGCACGGUGACACUGGCCUGCGAGCUAAGCCCAGCGUGUGCAGAGGUGGUGUGGCGCUGCGGCAACACGCAGCUUCGGGUGGGCAAGCGCUUCCAGAUGGUGGCCGAGGGGCCCGUGCGCUCACUCACUGUGUUGGGGCUGCGCGCAGAGGACGCAGGGGAGUACGUGUGUGAGAGCCGUGAUGACCACACCAGUGCGCAGCUCACCGUCAGUGUGCCCCGAGUGGUGAAGUUUAUGUCUGGGCUGAGCACCGUGGUCGCAGAGGAGGGCGGCGAGGCCACCUUCCAGUGCGUGGUGUCCCCCAGUGAUGUGGCAGUCGUGUGGUUCCGGGACGGUGCCCUGCUUCAGCCCAGCGAGAAGUUUGCCAUAUCACAGAGUGGCGCCAGCCACAGCCUGACCAUCUCAGACCUGGUGCUGGAGGACGCGGGCCAGAUCACCGUGGAGGCUGAGGGCGCCUCAUCCUCUGCUGCCCUGAGGGUCCGAGAGGCGCCUGUGCUGUUCAAAAAGAAGCUGGAGCCGCAGACGGUGGAGGAGCGGAGCUCGGUGACCCUGGAGGUGGAGCUGACGCGGCCGUGGCCGGAGCUGAGGUGGACACGGAACGCGACGGCCCUGGCGCCGGGAAAGAACGUGGAGAUCCACGCCGAGGGCGCCCGCCACCGCCUGGUUCUGCACAACGUAGGUUUUGCCGACCGUGGCUUCUUUGGCUGCGAGACGCCGGAUGACAAGACACAGGCCAAACUCACCGUGGAGAUGCGCCAGGUACGGCUCGUACGGGGCCUGCAGGCAGUGGAGGCACGGGAGCAGGGCACGGCUACCAUGGAGGUGCAGCUGUCGCAUGCGGACGUGGAUGGCAGCUGGACUCGUGACGGUCUGCGGUUCCAGCAGGGGCCCACGUGCCACCUGGCUGUGCGGGGCCCCAUGCACACCCUCACACUCUCGGGGCUGCGGCCAGAGGAUAGUGGCCUUAUGGUCUUCAAGGCCGAAGGAGUGCACACGUCGGCGCGGCUCGUGGUCACCGAGCUUCCCGUGAGCUUCAGCCGCCCGCUGCAGGACGUGGUGACCACUGAGAAGGAGAAGGUUACCCUGGAGUGCGAGCUGUCGCGUCCUAAUGUGGAUGUGCGCUGGCUGAAGGACGGUGUGGAGCUGCGGGCAGGCAAGACGAUGGCCAUCGCAGCCCAGGGCGCCUGCAGGAGCCUCACCAUUUACCGGUGCGAGUUCGCGGAUCAGGGAGUGUAUGUGUGUGAUGCCCAUGAUGCCCAGAGCUCUGCCUCCGUGAAGGUACAAGGCCGCAACAUCCAGAUCGUGAGGCCCCUGGAGGAUGUGGAAGUGAUGGAGAAGGACGGUGCCACCUUCUCCUGUGAGGUCUCCCACGACGAAGUGCCUGGCCAGUGGUUCUGGGAGGGCAGUAAACUGCGGCCCACUGACAACGUGCGCAUCCGCCAGGAAGGAAGGACAUACACUCUCAUCUACCGGAGAGUCCUGGCGGAAGAUGCAGGAGAGAUCCAAUUUGUAGCCGAAAAUGCAGAAUCGCGAGCCCAGCUCCGAGUGAAGGAGCUGCCAGUGACCCUCGUGCGCCCGCUGCGGGACAAGAUUGCCAUGGAGAAGCACCGCGGUGUGCUGGAGUGUCAGGUGUCCCGGGCCAGCGCCCAGGUGCGGUGGUUCAAGGGCAGUCAGGAGCUGCAGCCCGGGCCCAAGUACGAGCUGGUCAGUGAUGGCCUCUACCGCAAGCUGAUCAUCAGUGAUGUCCACGCAGAGGACGAGGACACCUACACCUGUGACGCCGGUGAUGUCAAGACCAGUGCACAGUUCUUCGUGGAAGAGCAAUCCAUCACCAUUGUGCGGGGUCUGCAGGACGUGACAGUGAUGGAGCCCGCUCCUGCCUGGUUUGAGUGUGAGACCUCCAUCCCCUCAGUGCGGCCACCUAAGUGGCUCCUGGGGAAGACGGUGUUGCAGGCUGGGGGGAACGUGGGCCUGGAGCAGGAGGGCACGGUGCACCGGCUGAUGCUGCGGCGGACCUGCUCCACCAUGACCGGGCCCGUGCACUUCACCGUUGGCAAGUCGCGCUCCUCUGCCCGCCUGGUGGUCUCAGACAUCCCCGUAGUCCUCACACGGCCGUUGGAGCCCAAGACAGGGCGUGAGCUGCAGUCAGUGGUCCUGUCCUGCGACUUCCGGCCAGCCCCCAAGGCUGUGCAGUGGUACAAGGAUGACACGCCCCUGUCUCCCUCUGAGAAGUUUAAGAUGAGCCUGGAGGGUCAGAUGGCUGAGCUGCGCAUCCUCCGGCUCAUGCCUGCUGAUGCUGGUGUCUACCGGUGCCAGGCGGGCAGUGCCCACAGCAGCACUGAGGUCACUGUGGAAGCGCGGGAGGUGACAGUGACAGGGCCGCUACAGGAUGCAGAGGCCACGGAGGAGGGCUGGGCCAGCUUCUCCUGUGAGCUGUCCCACGAGGAUGAGGAGGUCGAGUGGUCGCUCAACGGGAUGCCCCUGUACAACGACAGCUUCCAUGAGAUCUCACACAAGGGCCGGCGCCACACGCUGGUACUGAAGAGCAUCCAGCGGGCUGAUGCGGGCAUAGUACGCGCCUCCUCCCUGAAGGUGUCGACCUCUGCCCGCCUGGAGGUCCGAGUGAAGCCGGUGGUGUUCCUGAAGGCGCUGGAUGACCUGUCCGCAGAGGAGCGCGGCACCCUGGCCCUGCAGUGUGAAGUCUCUGACCCCGAGGCCCAUGUGGUGUGGCGCAAAGAUGGCGUGCAGCUGGGCCCCAGUGACAAGUAUGACUUCCUGCACACGGCGGGCACGCGGGGGCUCGUGGUGCAUGACGUGAGCCCUGAAGACGCCGGCCUGUACACCUGCCACGUGGGCUCCGAGGAGACCCGGGCCCGGGUCCGCGUGCACGAUCUGCACGUGGGCAUCACCAAGAGGCUGAAGACAAUGGAGGUGCUGGAAGGGGAAAGCUGCAGCUUUGAGUGCGUCCUGUCCCACGAGAGUGCCAGCGACCCGGCCAUGUGGACAGUCGGUGGGAAGACAGUGGGCAGCUCCAGCCGCUUCCAGGCCACACGUCAGGGCCGAAAAUACAUCCUGGUGGUCCGGGAGGCUGCACCAAGUGAUGCCGGGGAGGUGGUCUUCUCUGUGCGGGGCCUCACCUCCAAGGCCUCACUCAUUGUCAGAGAGAGGCCGGCCGCCAUCAUCAAGCCCCUGGAAGACCAGUGGGUGGCGCCAGGGGAGGACGUGGAGCUGCGCUGUGAGCUGUCACGGGCGGGAACGCCCGUGCACUGGCUGAAGGACAGGAAGGCCAUCCGCAAGAGCCAGAAGUAUGAUGUGGUCUGCGAGGGCACGAUGGCCAUGCUGGUCAUCCGCGGGGCCUCGCUCAAGGACGCGGGCGAGUACACGUGUGAGGUGGAGGCUUCCAAGAGCACAGCCAGCCUCCAUGUGGAAGAAAAAGCAAACUGCUUCACAGAGGAGCUGACCAAUCUGCAGGUGGAGGAGAAAGGCACAGCUGUGUUCACGUGCAAGACGGAGCACCCCGCGGCCACAGUGACCUGGCGCAAGGGCCUCUUGGAGCUACGGGCCUCAGGGAAGCACCAGCCCAGCCAGGAGGGCCUGACCCUGCGGCUCACCAUCAGUGCCCUGGAGAAGGCAGACAGCGACACCUAUACCUGCGACAUUGGCCAGGCCCAGUCCCGGGCCCAGCUCCUAGUGCAAGGCCGGAGAGUGCACAUCAUCGAGGACCUGGAGGAUGUGGAUGUGCAGGAGGGCUCCUCGGCCACCUUCCGUUGCCGGAUCUCCCCGGCCAACUACGAGCCUGUGCACUGGUUCCUGGACAAGACACCCCUGCAUGCCAACGAGCUCAAUGAGAUCGAUGCCCAGCCCGGGGGCUACCACGUGCUGACCCUGCGGCAGCUGGCGCUCAAGGACUCGGGCACCAUCUACUUUGAGGCGGGUGACCAGCGGGCCUCGGCCGCCCUGCGGGUCACUGAGAAGCCAAGCGUCUUCUCCCGGGAGCUCACAGAUGCCACCAUCACAGAGGGUGAGGACUUGACCCUGGUGUGCGAGACCAGCACCUGCGACAUUCCUGUGUGCUGGACCAAGGAUGGGAAGACCCUGCGGGGGUCUGCCCGGUGCCAGCUGAGCCAUGAGGGCCACCGGGCCCAGCUGCUCAUCACUGGGGCCACCCUGCAGGACAGUGGACGCUACAAGUGUGAGGCUGGGGGCGCCUGCAGCAGCUCCAUUGUCAGGGUGCAUGCGCGGCCAGUGCGGUUCCAGGAGGCCCUGAAGGACCUGGAGGUGCUGGAGGGUGGUGCUGCCACACUGCGCUGUGUGCUGUCAUCUGUGGCUGCGCCCGUGAAGUGGUGCUAUGGAAACAACGUCCUGAGGCCAGGUGACAAAUACAGCCUACGCCAGGAGGGUGCCAUGCUGGAGCUGGUGGUCCGGAACCUCCGGCCGCAGGACAGCGGGCGGUACUCAUGCUCCUUCGGGGACCAGACUACUUCUGCCACCCUCACAGUGACUGCCCUGCCUGCCCAGUUCAUCGGGAAACUGAGAAACAAGGAGGCCACAGAAGGGGCCACGGCCACGCUGCGGUGUGAGCUGAGCAAGGCAGCCCCUGUGGAGUGGAGAAAGGGGUCCGAGACCCUCAGAGAUGGGGACAGAUACUGUCUGAGGCAGGACGGGGCCAUGUGUGAGCUGCAGAUCCGUGGCCUGGCCAUGGUGGAUGCCGCGGAGUACUCGUGUGUGUGUGGAGAGGAGAGGACCUCAGCCUCACUCACCAUCAGGCCCAUGCCUGCCCACUUCAUAGGAAGACUGAGACACCAAGAGAGCAUAGAAGGGGCCACAGCCACGCUGCGGUGUGAGCUGAGCAAGGCGGCCCCCGUGGAGUGGAGGAAGGGGCGUGAGAGCCUCAGAGAUGGGGACAGACAUAGCCUGAGGCAGGACGGGGCUGUGUGCGAGCUGCAGAUCUGUGGCCUGGCUGUGGCAGAUGCUGGGGAGUACUCCUGUGUGUGUGGGGAGGAGAGGACCUCUGCCACUCUCACCGUGAAGGCCCUGCCAGCCAAGUUCACAGAGGGUCUGAGGAAUGAAGAGGCCGUGGAAGGGGCCACAGCCAUGUUGUGGUGUGAACUGAGCAAGGUGGCCCCUGUGGAGUGGAGGAAGGGGCCCGAGAACCUCAGAGAUGGGGACAGAUACAUCCUGAGGCAGGAGGGGACCAGGUGUGAGCUGCAGAUCUGUGGCCUGGCCAUGGCGGACGCCGGGGAGUACUUGUGUGUGUGCGGGCAGGAGAGGACCUCAGCCACGCUCACCAUCAGGGCUCUGCCUGCCAGGUUCAUAGAAGAUGUGAAAAACCAGGAGGCCAGAGAAGGGGCCACAGCUGUGCUGCAGUGUGAGCUGAACAGUGCAGCCCCUGUGGAGUGGAGAAAGGGGUCUGAGACCCUUAGAGAUGGGGACAGAUACAGCCUGAGGCAGGACGGGACUAAAUGUGAGCUGCAGAUUCGUGGCCUGGCCAUGGCAGACACUGGGGAGUACUCGUGCGUGUGCGGGCAGGAGAGGACCUCGGCUAUGCUCACCGUCAGGGCUCUACCCAUCAAGUUCACAGAGGGUCUGAGGAACGAAGAGGCCACAGAAGGGGCAACAGCCGUGCUGCGGUGUGAGCUGAGCAAGAUGGCCCCCGUGGAGUGGUGGAAGGGGCAUGAGACCCUCAGAGAUGGAGACAGACACAGCCUGAGGCAGGACGGGGCCAGGUGUGAGCUGCAGAUCCGCGGCCUCGUGGCAGAGGACGCUGGGGAGUACCUGUGCAUGUGCGGGAAGGAGAGGACCUCAGCCAUGCUCACCGUCAGGGCCAUGCCUUCCAAGUUCAUAGAGGGUCUGAGGAAUGAAGAGGCCACAGAAGGGGACACGGCCACGCUGUGGUGUGAGCUGAGCAAGGCGGCACCGGUGGAGUGGAGGAAGGGGCAUGAGACCCUCAGAGAUGGGGACAGACACAGCCUGAGGCAGGACGGGUCCAGGUGUGAGCUGCAGAUCCGUGGCCUGGCUGUGGUGGAUGCCGGGGAGUACUCGUGUGUGUGCGGGCAGGAGAGGACCUCAGCCACACUCACUGUCAGGGCCCUGCCUGCCAGAUUCAUAGAAGAUGUGAAAAACCAGGAGGCCAGAGAAGGGGCCACGGCCGUGCUGCAAUGUGAGCUGAGCAAGGCGGCCCCCGUGGAGUGGAGGAAGGGGUCUGAGACCCUCAGAGGUGGGGACAGAUACAGCCUGAGGCAGGAUGGGACCAGAUGUGAGCUGCAGAUUCAUGGCCUGUCUGUGGCAGACACUGGGGAGUACUCGUGUGUGUGCGGGCAGGAGAGGACCUCGGCCACACUCACCGUCAGGGCCCUGCCUGCACGAUUCACUCAAGAUCUGAAGACCAAGGAGGCCUCAGAAGGGGCCACAGCUACACUGCAGUGUGAGCUGAGCAAGGUGGCCCCUGUGGAAUGGAAGAAGGGUCCUGAGACCCUCAGAGAUGGGGGCAGAUACAGCCUGAAGCAGGAUGGGACGAGGUGUGAGCUGCAGAUCCAUGACCUGUCUGUGGCGGAUGCUGGGGAAUACUCAUGCAUGUGUGGACAAGAGAGGACCUCGGCCACGCUCACUGUCAGGGCCCUGCCUGCCAGGUUCACAGAGGGUCUGAGGAAUGAAGAGGCCAUGGAAGGGGCCACAGCCACACUGCAAUGUGAGCUGAGCAAGGCAGCCCCUGUGGAGUGGAGGAAAGGCCUUGAGGCUCUCAGAGAUGGGGACAAAUACAGCCUGAGACAAGACGGGGCUGUGUGUGAGCUGCAGAUUCAUGGCCUGGCUAUGGCAGAUAACGGGGUGUACUCAUGUGUGUGUGGGCAGGAGAGGACCUCAGCUACACUCACUGUCAGGGCCCUGCCUGCCAGAUUCAUAGAGGAUAUGAGAAACCAGAAGGCCACAGAAGGGGCUACAGUCACAUUGCAAUGUAAGCUGAGAAAGGCGGCCCCCGUGGAGUGGAGAAAGGGGCCCAACACCCUCAAAGAUGGGGACAGGUACAGCCUGAAGCAGGAUGGGACCAGUUGUGAGCUGCAGAUUCGUGGCCUGGUCAUAGCAGAUGCUGGAGAAUACUCGUGCAUAUGUGAGCAGGAGAGGACCUCGGCCACGCUCACUGUCAGGGCCCUGCCGGCCAGAUUCAUAGAAGAUGUGAGAAAUCACGAGGCCACAGAAGGGGCCACAGCUGUGCUGCAGUGUGAGCUGAGCAAGGCGGCCCCCGUGGAGUGGCGGAAGGGGUCUGAGACCCUCAGAGAUGGGGACAGAUAUAGCCUGAGGCAGGACGGGACGAGGUGUGAGCUGCAGAUUCGUGGCCUGGCUGUGGAGGACACUGGAGAGUAUUUGUGUGUGUGCGGGCAGGAGAGAACCUCAGCUACACUCACUGUCAGGGCCCUGCCAGCCAGAUUCAUAGACAACAUGACAAACCAGGAGGCCAGAGAAGGGGCCACGGCCACACUGCACUGUGAACUGAGCAAGGUGGCCCCUGUGGAGUGGAGGAAGGGACCUGAAACCCUCCGAGAUGGGGACAGACACAGCCUGAGGCAGGAUGGGACCAGGUGUGAGCUGCAGAUUCGUGGCCUGUCUGUGGCAGAUGCCGGGGAGUACUCGUGCGUGUGUGGGCAGGAGAGGACCUCAGCCACACUCACGAUCAGGGCCCUGCCCGCCAAGUUCACAAAGGGUCUGAGGAAUGAAGAGGCCACAGAAGGGGCCACGGCUAUGUUGCAGUGUGAGCUGAGCAAGGUGGCCCCUGUUGAGUGGAGGAAGGGACCUGAAACCCUCAGAGAUGGGGACAGAUACAACCUGAGGCAGGAUGGGACCAGAUGUGAGCUGCAGAUUCAUGGCCUGUCCGUGGCAGACACUGGGGAGUACUCAUGUGUAUGUGGUCAGGAGAAGACGUCGGCCACUCUCACUGUCAAGGCCCCACAGCCAGUGUUCCGGGAGCCGCUGCAGAGUCUGCAGGCGGAGGAGGGCUCCACGGCCACCCUGCAGUGUGAGCUGUCUGAGCCCACUGCUACAGUGGUCUGGAGCAAGGGUGGCCUGCAGCUGCAGGCCAAUGGGCGCCGGGAGCCACGGCUUCAGGGCUGCACCGCGGAGCUGGUGUUACAGGACCUACAACGUGAAGACACUGGCGAAUACACUUGCACCUGUGGCUCCCAGGCCACCAGUGCCACCCUCACUGUCACAGCUGCGCCUGUGCGGUUCCUCCGAGAGCUGCAGCACCAGGAGGUGGAUGAGGGAGGCACCGCACACUUAUGCUGCGAGCUGAGCCGGGCGGGUGCGAGCGUGGAGUGGCGCAAGGGCUCCCUACAGCUCUUCCCUUGUGCCAAGUACCAGAUGGUGCAGGAUGGUGCAGCUGCAGAGCUGCUGGUACGCGGAGUGGAGCAGGAGGAUGCGGGUGACUACACGUGUGACACGGGCCACACGCAGAGCAUGGCCAGCCUCUCUGUCCGUGUCCCCAGGCCCAAGUUCAAGACCCGGCUUCAGAGUCUGGAGCAGGAGACAGGUGACAUAGCCCGGCUGUGCUGUCAGCUGAGUGAUGCAGAGUCGGGGGCCGUGGUGCAAUGGCUCAAGGAGGGCGUGGAGCUGCAUGCGGGCCCCAAGUACGAGAUGCGGAGCCAGGGGGCCACGCGGGAGCUGCUGAUCCACCAACUGGAGGCCAAGGACACGGGCGAGUAUGCCUGUGUGACAGGCGGCCAGAAAACCGCUGCCUCCCUCAGGGUCACAGAGCCUGAGGUGACCAUUGUACGGGGGCUGGUUGAUGCGGAGGUGACGGCCGAUGAGGAUGUUGAGUUCAGCUGUGAGGUGUCCAGGGCUGGAGCCACAGGCGUGCAGUGGUGCCUACAGGGCCUGCCACUGCAAAGCAAUGAGGUGACAGAGGUGGCUGUGCGGGAUGGCCGCAUCCACACCCUGCGGCUGAAGGGCGUGACGCCCGAGGACGCUGGCACUGUCUCCUUCCAUUUGGGAAACCAUGCUUCCUCUGCCCAGCUCACCGUCAGAGCUCCUGAGGUGACCAUCCUGGAGCCCCUGCAGGACGUGCAGCUCAGUGAGGGCCAGGAUGCCAGCUUCCAGUGCCGGCUAUCCAGAGCUUCAGGCCAGGAGGCCCGCUGGGCUUUAGGAGGGGUGCCCCUGCAGGCCAACGAGAUGAAUGACAUCACUGUGGAGCAGGGCACACUCCACCUGCUCACCCUGCACAAGGUGACCCUUGAGGAUGCUGGAACUGUCAGUUUCCACGUGGGCACGUGUAGCUCUGAGGCCCAGCUGAAAGUCACAGCCAAGAACACGGUGGUGCGGGGGCUGGAGAAUGUGGAGGCGCUGGAGGGCGGCGAGGCGCUGUUCGAGUGCCAGCUGUCCCAGCCCGAGGUGGCCGCCCACACCUGGCUGCUGGACGACGAACCCGUGCACACCUCGGAGAACGCCGAGGUGGUCUUCUUCGAGAACGGCCUGCGCCACCUGCUGCUGCUCAAAAACUUGCGGCCACAAGACAGCUGCCGGGUGACCUUCCUGGCUGGGGAUAUGGUGACGUCCGCAUUCCUCACGGUCCGAGGCUGGCGCCUGGAGAUCCUGGAGCCUCUGAAAAACGCGGCGGUCCGGGCCGGCGCACAGGCAUGCUUCACCUGCACGCUCAGCGAGGCGGUGCCCGUGGGAGAGGCGUCCUGGUACAUCAAUGGCGCGGCAGUGCAGCCGGAUGACAGCGACUGGACUGUCACCGCCGACGGCAGUCACCACGCCCUACUGCUGCGCAGCGCCCAGCCCCACCACGCCGGGGAGGUCACCUUCGCUUGCCGCGACGCCGUGGCCUCUGCGCGGCUCACCGUGCUGGGCCUCCCUGAUCCCCCAGAGGAUGCUGAGGUGGUGGCUCGCAGCAGCCACACUGUGACACUGUCUUGGGCAGCUCCCAUGAGUGAUGGAGGCGGUGGUCUCUGUGGCUACCGCGUGGAGGUGAAGGAGGGGGCCACAGGCCAGUGGCGGCUGUGCCACGAGCUGGUGCCUGGACCCGAGUGUGUGGUGGAUGGCCUGGCCCCCGGGGAGACCUACCGCUUCCGUGUGGCAGCUGUGGGCCCUGUGGGUGCUGGGGAACCGGUUCACCUGCCCCAGACAGUGCGGCUUGCAGAGCCACCGAAGCCUGUGCCUCCCCAGCCCUCAGCCCCUGAGAGCCGGCAGGUGGCAGCUGGUGAAGAUGUCUCUCUGGAGCUUGAGGUGGUGGCUGAGGCUGGUGAGGUCAUCUGGCACAAGGGAAUGGAGCGCAUCCAGCCCGGUGGGCGGUUCGAGGUGGUCUCCCAGGGUCGGCAACAGAUGCUGGUGAUCAAGGGCUUCACGGCAGAAGACCAGGGCGAGUACCACUGUGGCCUGGCUCAGGGCUCCAUCUGCCCUGCGGCUGCCACCUUCCAGGUGGCACUGAGCCCAGCCUCUGUGGAUGAGGCCCCUCAGCCCAGCUUGCCCCCCGAGGCAGCCCAGGAGGGUGACCUGCACCUACUGUGGGAGGCCCUGGCUCGGAAACGUCGCAUGAGCCGUGAGCCCACGCUGGACUCCAUUAGCGAGCUGCCAGAGGAGGACGGCCGCUCGCAGCGCCUGCCACAGGAGGCAGAGGAGGUGGCACCUGAUCUCUCUGAAGGCUACUCCACGGCCGAUGAGCUGGCCCGCACUGGAGAUGCUGACCUCUCACACACCAGCUCUGAUGAUGAGUCCCGGGCAGGCACCCCUUCCCUGGUCACCUACCUCAAGAAGGCUGGGAGGCCAGGCACCUCACCACUGGCCAGCAAGGUUGGGGCCCCAGCAGCCCCCUCUGUGAAGCCACAGCAGCAGCAGGAGCCACUGGCUGCUGUGCGCCCACCACUGGGAGACCUGAGCACCAAAGACCUGGGUGAUCCCUCAAUGGACAAGGCAGCUGUGAAGAUCCAGGCUGCCUUUAAGGGCUACAAGGUCCGGAAGGAGAUGAAGCAGCAGGAAGGGCCCAUGUUCUCCCACACAUUUGGGGACACCGAGGCACAGGUGGGGGAUGCCCUGCGGCUGGAGUGUGUCGUGGCCAGCAAGGCAGAUGUGCGAGCCCGCUGGCUGAAGGAUGGUGUGGAGCUGACCGAUGGGCGGCACCAUCACAUCGACCAGCUUGGGGAUGGCACCUGCUCUCUGCUGAUCACUGGCCUGGACCGUGCUGAUGCUGGCUGCUACACCUGUCAGGUGAGCAACAAGUUUGGCCAGGUGACCCACAGUGCCUGUGUGGUGGUCAGUGGGUCAGAGAGUGAAGCCGAGAGCUCCUCUGGGGGUGAGCUGGACGAUGCCUUCCGCCGGGCUGCCCGUCGGCUGCACCGGCUCUUCCGCACCAAAAGUCCGGCUGAAGUUUCAGAUGAGGAGCUCUUCCUGAGUGCAGACGAGGGCCCUGCAGAGCCAGAGGAGCCCGCGGACUGGCAGACAUACCGCGAAGAUGAGCAUUUCAUCUGCAUCCGUUUUGAGGCGCUCACUGAGGCCCGCCAGGCGGUAACUCGCUUCCAGGAGAUGUUUGCCACACUGGGCAUUGGGGUGGAGAUCAAGCUGGUGGAACAGGGGCCUCGGAGGGUAGAGAUGUGCAUCAGCAAAGAGACUCCUGCCCCUGUGGUGCCUCCAGAGCCAUUGCCCAGCCUACUGACUUCUGACGCUGCCCCAGUGUUCCUGACUGAGUUGCAGAACCAAGAAGUGCAGGAUGGGUAUCCUGUGAGCUUUGACUGCGUGGUGACAGGUCAGCCCAUGCCCAGUGUGCGCUGGUUCAAGGAUGGGAAGUUGUUGGAGGAGGAUGAUCACUACAUGAUUAAUGAAGACCAACAGGGUGGCCAUCAGCUCAUCAUCACAGCCGUGGUGCCAGCAGACAUGGGCGUCUACCGCUGCCUGGCCGAGAACAGCAUGGGUGUCUCCUCCACCAAGGCUGAGCUCCGUGUGGACUUGACAAGCACAGACUAUGACACUGCAGCAGAUGCCACGGAGUCCUCAUCCUACUUCAGUGCCCAAGGCUACCUGUCCAGCCGGGAGCAGGAGGGAACAGAGUCCACCACUGAUGAGGGCCAGCUGCCCCAGGUGGUGGAGGAGCUGAGAGACCUCCAGGUGGCCCCUGGCACACGCCUGGCCAAGUUCCAGCUCAAGGUGAAAGGCUACCCUGCUCCCAGAUUAUACUGGUUCAAAGAUGGCCAGCCCCUGACCGCAUCUGCCCACAUCCGCAUGACUGACAAGAAGAUCCUGCACACCCUGGAGAUCAUCUCCGUCACCCGGGAGGACUCUGGCCAGUAUGCAGCCUAUAUCAGCAAUGCCAUGGGUGCUGCCUACUCGUCUGCCCGGCUGCUGGUUCGAGGCCCUGAUGAGCCAGAAGAGAAGCCUGCAUCAGAUGUGCAUGAGCAGCUGGUGCCGCCCCGAAUGCUGGAGAGGUUCACCCCCAAGAAAGUGAAGAAAGGCUCCAGCAUCACCUUCUCUGUGAAGGUAGAAGGACGCCCGGUGCCCACCGUGCACUGGCUCAGGGAGGAGGCUGAGAGAGGCGUGCUGUGGAUUGGCCCUGACACACCGGGCUACACCGUGGCCAGCUCUGCGCAGCAGCACAGCCUGGUCCUGCUGGACGUGGGCCGGCAGCACCAGGGCACCUACACAUGCAUUGCCAGCAACGCUGCCGGCCAGGCCCUCUGCUCCGCCAGCCUGCACGUCUCGGGCCUGCCUAAGGUGGAGGAGCAGGAGAAAGUGAAGGAAGCGCUGAUUUCCACUUUCCUGCAGGGGACCACACAAGCCAUCUCAGCACAGGGGUUGGAAACUGCGAGUUUUGCUGACCUUGGUGGGCAGAGGAAAGAAGAGCCUCUGGCUGCCAAGGAGGCCCUCGGCCACCUGUCCCUCGCUGAGGUGGGCACAGAGGAGUUCCUGCAGAAACUGACCUCCCAGAUCACUGAGAUGGUAUCGGCCAAGAUCACGCAGGCCAAGCUGCAGGUGCCCGGAGGUGACAGUGAUGAGGACUCCAAGACACCAUCUGCAUCCCCCCGCCAUGGCCGAUCACGGCCAUCCUCCAGCAUCCAGGAGUCUUCCUCAGAGUCAGAGGACGGCGAUGCCCGAGGCGAGAUCUUUGACAUCUACGUGGUCACCGCUGACUACCUGCCCCUAGGGGCUGAGCAGGAUGCCAUCACGCUGCGGGAAGGCCAGUAUGUGGAGGUCCUGGAUGCAGCCCACCCACUGCGCUGGCUUGUCCGCACCAAGCCCACCAAGUCCAGCCCCUCACGGCAGGGCUGGGUGUCACCAGCCUACCUGGACAGGAGGCUCAAGCUGUCACCUGAGUGGGGGGCCGCUGAGGCCCCUGAGUUCCCUGGGGAGGCUGUGUCUGAAGACGAAUACAAGGCAAGGCUGAGCUCUGUGAUCCAGGAGCUGCUGAGUUCUGAGCAGGCCUUCGUGGAGGAGCUGCAGUUCCUGCAGAGCCACCACCUGCAGCACCUGGAGCGCUGCCCCCACGUGCCCAUAGCUGUGGCCGGCCAGAAGGCAGUCAUCUUCCGCAAUGUGCGGGACAUCGGCCGCUUCCACAGCAGCUUCCUGCAGGAGUUGCAGCAGUGCGACACGGACGACGACGUGGCCAUGUGCUUCAUCAAGAACCAGGCGGCCUUUGAGCAGUACCUGGAGUUCCUGGUGGGGCGUGUGCAGGCUGAGUCGGUGGUCGUCAGCACGGCCAUCCAGGAGUUCUACAAGAAAUACGCGGAGGAGGCCCUGUUGGCAGGGGACCCCUCUCAGCCCCCGCCACCACCUCUGCAGCACUACCUGGAGCAGCCAGUGGAGCGGGUGCAGCGCUACCAGGCCUUGCUGAAGGAGCUGAUCCGCAACAAGGCGCGGAACAGACAGAACUGCGCGCUGCUGGAGCAGGCCUAUGCCGUGGUGUCUGCCCUGCCACAGCGCGCUGAGAACAAGCUGCACGUGUCCCUCAUGGAGAACUACCCAGGCACCCUGCAGGCCCUGGGCGAGCCCAUCCGCCAGGGCCACUUCAUCGUGUGGGAGGGUGCACCGGGGGCCCGCAUGCCCUGGAAGGGCCACAACCGUCACGUGUUCCUCUUCCGCAACCACCUGGUAAUCUGCAAGCCCCGGCGAGACUCCCGCACCGAUACCGUCAGCUACGUGUUCCGGAACAUGAUGAAGCUGAGCAGCAUCGACCUGAACGACCAGGUGGAGGGGGAUGACCGCGCCUUCGAGGUGUGGCAGGAGCGGGAGGACUCGGUGCGCAAGUACCUGCUGCAGGCACGGACAGCCAUUAUCAAGAGCUCGUGGGUGAAGGAGAUCUGUGGCAUCCAGCAGCGUCUGGCCCUGCCUGUGUGGCGGCCCCCGGACUUUGAAGAGGAGCUGGCCGACUGCACAGCCGAGCUGGGUGAGACAGUCAAGCUGGCCUGCCGCGUGACGGGCACACCCAAGCCUGUCAUCAGCUGGUACAAAGAUGGGAAAGCAGUGCAGGUGGACCCCCACCACAUCCUCAUUGAAGACCCUGAUGGCUCGUGUGCACUCAUCCUGGACAGCCUGACCGGUGUGGACUCUGGCCAGUACAUGUGCUUCGCGGCCAGCGCCGCUGGCAACUGCAGUACCCUGGGCAAGAUCCUGGUGCAAGUCCCACCACGGUUCGUGAACAAGGUCCGGGCCUCACCCUUUGUGGAGGGAGAGGACGCCCAGUUCACCUGCACCAUCGAAGGCGCCCCGUACCCGCAGAUCAGGUGGUACAAGGACGGGGCCCUGCUGACCACUGGCAACAAGUUCCAGACACUGAGUGAGCCUCGCAGCGGCCUGCUAGUGCUGGUGAUCCGGGCGGCCAGCAAGGAGGACCUGGGGCUCUACGAGUGUGAGCUGGUGAACCGGCUGGGCUCCGCGCGGGCUAGUGCGGAGCUGCGCAUUCAGAGCCCCAUGCUGCAGGCCCAGGAGCAGUGUCACAGGGAGCAGCUCGUGGCUGCAGUGGAAGACACCACCCUGGAGCGAGCGGACCAGGAGGUCACAUCUGUCCUGAAGAGACUGCUGGGCCCCAAGGCGCCAGGCCCCUCCACAGGGGACCUCACUGGCCCUGGCCCCUGCCCCAGGGGGGCACCCGCACUCCAGGAAACCGGCUCCCAGCCCCCAGUCACCGGAACUUCGGAGGCACCUGCCGUGCCCCCGAGGGUGCCACAGCCCCUCCUCCACGAAGGCCCAGAGCAGGAGCCGGAGGCCAUUGCCAGAGCCCAGGAAUGGACUGUGCCCAUUCGGAUGGAGGGUGCAGCCUGGCCCGGGGCAGGCACAGGGGAGCUGCUCUGGGACGUCCACAGCCACGUGGUCAGAGAGACCACACAGAGGACCUACACAUACCAGGCCAUCGACACGCACACCGCACGGCCCCCAUCCAUGCAGGUAACCAUCGAGGAUGUGCAGGCACAGACAGGCGGAACGGCCCAAUUCGAGGCUAUCAUUGAGGGCGACCCACAGCCCUCGGUGACCUGGUACAAGGACAGCGUCCAGCUGGUGGACAGCACCCGGCUUAGCCAGCAGCAAGAAGGCACCACAUACUCCCUGGUGCUGAGGCAUGUGGCCUCGAAGGAUGCCGGCGUUUACACCUGCCUGGCCCAAAACACUGGUGGCCAGGUGCUCUGCAAGGCAGAGCUGCUGGUGCUUGGGGGGGACAAUGAGCCGGACUCAGAGAAGCAAAGCCACCGGAGGAAGCUGCACUCCUUCUAUGAGGUCAAGGAGGAGAUUGGAAGGGGCGUGUUUGGCUUCGUAAAAAGAGUGCAGCACAAAGGAAACAAGAUCUUGUGCGCUGCCAAGUUCAUCCCCCUACGGAGCAGAACUCGGGCCCAGGCAUACAGGGAGCGAGACAUCCUGGCCGCGCUGAGCCACCCGCUGGUCACGGGGCUGCUGGACCAGUUUGAGACCCGCAAGACCCUCAUCCUCAUCCUGGAGCUGUGCUCAUCCGAGGAGCUGCUGGACCGCCUGUACAGGAAGGGCGUGGUGACGGAGGCCGAGGUCAAGGUCUACAUCCAGCAGCUGGUGGAGGGGCUGCACUACCUGCACAGCCAUGGCGUUCUCCACCUGGACAUAAAGCCCUCUAACAUCCUGAUGGUGCAUCCUGCCCGGGAAGACAUUAAAAUCUGCGACUUUGGCUUUGCCCAGAACAUCACCCCAGCAGAGCUGCAGUUCAGCCAGUACGGCUCCCCUGAGUUCGUCUCCCCCGAGAUCAUCCAGCAGAACCCUGUGAGCGAAGCCUCCGACAUUUGGGCCAUGGGUGUCAUCUCCUACCUCAGCCUGACCUGCUCAUCCCCAUUUGCCGGCGAGAGUGACCGUGCCACCCUCCUGAACGUCCUGGAGGGGCGCGUGUCAUGGAGCAGCCCCAUGGCUGCCCACCUCAGCGAAGACGCCAAAGACUUCAUCAAGGCUACGCUGCAGAGAGCCCCUCAGGCCCGGCCUAGUGCGGCCCAGUGCCUCUCCCACCCCUGGUUCCUGAAAUCCAUGCCUGCGGAGGAGGCCCACUUCAUCAACACCAAGCAGCUCAAGUUCCUCCUGGCCCGAAGUCGCUGGCAGCGUUCCCUGAUGAGCUACAAGUCCAUCCUGGUGAUGCGCUCCAUCCCUGAGCUGCUGCGGGGCCCACCCGACAGCCCCUCCCUCGGCGUAGCCCGGCACCUCUGCAGGGACACUGGUGGCUCCUCCAGUUCCUCCUCCUCCUCUGACAACGAGCUCGCCCCAUUUGCCCGGGCUAAGUCACUGCCACCCUCCCCGGUGACACACUCACCACUGCUGCACCCCCGGGGCUUCCUGCGGCCCUCGGCCAGCCUGCCUGAGGAAGCCGAGGCCAGUGAGCGCUCCACCGAGGCCCCAGCUCCGCCUGCAUCUCCCGAGGGUGCCGGGCCACCGGCCGCCCAGGGCUGCGUGCCCCGGCACAGCGUCAUCCGCAGCCUGUUCUACCACCAGGCGGGUGAGAGCCCUGAGCACGGGGCCCUGGCCCCGGGGAGCAGGCGGCACCCGGCCCGGCGGCGGCACCUGCUGAAGGGCGGGUACAUUGCGGGGGCGCUGCCAGGCCUGCGCGAGCCACUGAUGGAGCACCGCGUGCUGGAGGAGGAGGCCGCCAGGGAGGAGCAGGCCACCCUCCUGGCCAAAGCCCCCUCAUUCGAGACUGCCCUCCGGCUGCCUGCCUCUGGCACCCACUUGGCCCCUGGCCACAGCCACUCCCUGGAACAUGACUCUCCGAGCACCCCCCGCCCCUCCUCGGAGGCCUGCGGUGAGGCACAGCGACUGCCUUCAGCCCCCUCCGGGGGGGCCCCUAUCAGGGACAUGGGGCACCCUCAGGGCUCCAAGCAGCUUCCAUCCACUGGUGGCCACCCAGGCACUGCUCAGCCAGAGAGGCCAUCCCCGGACAGCCCUUGGGGGCAGCCAGCCCCUUUCUGCCACCCCAAGCAGGGUUCUGCCCCCCAGGAGGGCUGCAGCCCCCACCCAGCAGUUGCCCCAUGCCCUCCUGGCUCCUUCCCUCCAGGAUCUUGCAAAGAGGCCCCCUUAGUACCCUCAAGCCCCUUCUUGGGACAGCCCCAGGCACCCCCUGCCCCUGCCAAAGCAAGCCCCCCAUUGGACUCUAAGAUGGGGCCUGGAGACAUCUCUCUUCCUGGGAGGCCAAAACCCGGCCCCUGCAGUUCCCCAGGGUCAGCCUCCCAGGCGAGCUCUUCCCAAGUGAGCUCCCUCAGGGUGGGCUCCUCCCAGGUGGGCACAGAGCCUGGCCCCUCCCUGGAUGCGGAGGGCUGGACCCAGGAGGCUGAGGAUCUGUCCGACUCCACACCCACCUUGCAGCGGCCUCAGGAACAGGCGACCAUGCGCAAGUUCUCCCUGGGUGGUCGCGGGGGCUACGCAGGCGUGGCUGGCUAUGGCACCUUUGCCUUUGGUGGAGAUGCAGGGGGCAUGCUGGGGCAGGGGCCCAUGUGGGCCAGGAUAGCCUGGGCUGUGUCCCAGUCAGAGGAGGAGGAGCAGGAGGAGGCCAGGGCUGAGUCCCAGUCGGAGGAGCAGCAGGAGGCCAGGGCUGAGAGCCCACUGCCCCAGGUCAGUGCAAGGCCUGUGCCUGAGGUCGGCAGGGCUCCCACCAGGAGCUCUCCAGAGCCCACCCCAUGGGAGGACAUCGGGCAGGUCUCCCUGGUGCAGAUCCGGGACCUGUCAGGUGAUGCGGAGGCGGCCGACACAAUAUCCCUGGACAUUUCCGAGGUGGACCCCGCCUACCUCAACCUCUCAGACCUGUACGAUAUCAAGUACCUCCCAUUCGAGUUUAUGAUCUUCAGGAAAGUCCCCAAGUCCGCUCAGCCAGAGCCGCCCUCCCCCAUGGCUGAGGAGGAGCUGGCCGAGUUCCCGGAGCCCACGUGGCCCUGGCCAGGUGAACUGGGCCCCCACGCAGGCCUGGAGAUCACAGAGGAGUCAGAGGAUGUGGACGCGCUGCUGGCAGAGGCUGCCGUGGGCAGGAAGCGCAAGUGGUCCUCGCCGUCACGCAGCCUCUUCCACUUCCCUGGGAGGCACCUGCCGCUGGAUGAGCCUGCAGAGCUGGGGCUGCGUGAGAGAGUGAAGGCCUCCGUGGAGCACAUCUCCCGGAUCCUGAAGGGCAGGCCGGAAGGUCUGGAGAAGGAGGGGCCCCCCAGGAAGAAGCCAGGCCUUGCUUCCUUCCGGCUCUCAGGUCUGAAGAGCUGGGACCGAGCGCCGACAUUCCUAAGGGAGCUCUCAGAUGAGACUGUGGUCCUGGGCCAGUCAGUGACACUGGCCUGCCAGGUGUCAGCCCAGCCAGCUGCCCAGGCCACCUGGAGCAAAGACGGAGCCCCCCUGGAGAGCAGCAGCCGUGUCCUCAUCUCUGCCACCCUCAAGAACUUCCAGCUUCUGACCAUCCUGGUGGUGGUGGCUGAGGACCUGGGUGUGUACACCUGCAGCGUGAGCAAUGCGCUGGGGACAGUGACCACCACGGGCGUCCUCCGGAAGGCAGAGCGCCCCUCAUCUUCGCCAUGCCCGGAUAUCGGGGAGGUGUACGCGGAUGGGGUGCUGCUGGUCUGGAAGCCCGUGGAAUCCUACGGCCCUGUGACCUACAUUGUGCAGUGCAGCCUAGAAGGCGGCAGCUGGACCACACUGGCCUCCGACAUCUUUGACUGCUGCUACCUGACCAGCAAGCUCUCCCGGGGUGGCACCUACACCUUCCGCACGGCAUGUGUCAGCAAGGCAGGAAUGGGUCCCUACAGCAGCCCCUCGGAGCAAGUCCUCCUGGGAGGGCCCAGCCACCUGGCCUCUGAGGAGGAGAGCCAGGGGCGGUCAGCCCAACCCCUGCCCAGCACAAAGACCUUCGCAUUCCAGACACAGAUCCAGAGGGGCCGCUUCAGCGUGGUGCGGCAAUGCUGGGAGAAGGCCAGCGGGCGGGCGCUGGCCGCCAAGAUCAUCCCCUACCACCCCAAGGACAAGACAGCAGUGCUGCGCGAAUACGAGGCCCUCAAGGGCCUGCGCCACCCGCACCUGGCCCAGCUGCACGCAGCCUACCUCAGCCCCCGGCACCUGGUGCUCAUCUUGGAGCUGUGCUCUGGGCCCGAGCUGCUCCCCUGCCUGGCCGAGAGGGCCUCCUACUCAGAAUCCGAGGUGAAGGACUACCUGUGGCAGAUGUUGAGUGCCACCCAGUACCUGCACAACCAGCACAUCCUGCACCUGGACCUGAGGUCCGAGAACAUGAUCAUCACCGAAUACAACCUGCUCAAGGUCGUGGACCUGGGCAAUGCACAGAGCCUCAGCCAGGAGAAGGUGCUGCCCUCAGACAAGUUCAAGGACUACCUAGAGACCAUGGCUCCAGAGCUCCUGGAGGGCCAGGGGGCUGUUCCACAGACAGACAUCUGGGCCAUCGGUGUGACAGCCUUCAUCAUGCUGAGCGCCGAGUACCCGGUGAGCAGCGAGGGUGCACGCGACCUGCAGAGAGGACUGCGCAAGGGGCUGGUCCGGCUGAGCCGCUGCUACGCGGGGCUGUCCGGGGGCGCCGUGGCCUUCCUGCGCAGCACUCUGUGCGCCCAGCCCUGGGGCCGGCCCUGCGCGUCCAGCUGCCUGCAGUGCCCGUGGCUAACAGAGGAGGGCCCGGCCUGUUCGCGGCCCGCGCCCGUGACCUUCCCUACCGCGCGGCUGCGCGUCUUCGUGCGCAAUCGCGAGAAGAGACGCGCGCUGCUGUACAAGAGGCACAACCUGGCCCAGGUGCGCUGAGGGUCGCCCCGGCCACACCCUUGGUCUCCCCGCUGGGGGUCGCUGCAGACGCGCCAAUAAAAACGCACAGCCGGGCGAGAA